GUUAAUCAUUCCCAGCUCAAAGCCUUGUGCAAGUGCUCUCUGCCUUCACGCUUGCUUCCUUUGGGAGAGAACCUUCCUCUUCUUGAUCGGGGAUUCAGGAAGGAGCCCAGGAGCAGAGGAAGUAGAGAGAGAGACAACAUGUUACAUCUGCACCAUUCUUGAGACAGGGUCUCACCAUGUUGCUCAAGCUGGUCUUAAACACCUGGGCUCAGGCAAUGCUCCCACCUUGGCCUCCCAACGUGCUCAGAUAAUGGGCAUGAGCCACCACGCCUGACCGCUUCUGGAUCUCUUGAUGGUGCUUUCUCAGAAUGCACUGAUAGUGAUUUAUCCUGCAUCUGGAGAAUGAAGCAUGAGACCCGUGAUUAAUAGAUGUGCUCCAGGCUCCCUUGAUUUGAUGUUGCCCCAGGCAGCCUCAGAAGGAAUUGUAUUUCAUUCUCUGCAAAUCAGUUUGUGUUUCAGGAGCUGGCUGCCAGCGAUGCUCGCUGUACUGCUAAGUUUGGCACCAUCAGCUUCCAGCGACAUUUCCGCCUCCCGACCGAACAUCCUUCUUCUGAUGGCGGACGACCUUGGCAUUGGGGACAUUGGCUGCUAUGGCAACAACACCAUGAGGACUCCGAAUAUUGACCGCCUUGCAGAGGACGGCGUGAAGCUGACCCAACACAUCUCUGCCGCAUCUUUGUGCACCCCAAGCAGAGCCGCCUUCCUCACGGGCAGAUACCCUGUGCGAUCAGGGAUGGUUUCCAGCAUUGGUUACCGUGUUCUUCAGUGGACCGGAGCAUCUGGAGGUCUUCCAACAAAUGAGACAACUUUUGCAAAAAUACUGAAAGAGAAAGGCUAUGCCACUGGACUCAUUGGAAAAUGGCAUCUGGGUCUCAACUGUGAGUCAGCCAGUGAUCAUUGCCACCACCCUCUCCAUCAUGGCUUUGACCAUUUCUACGGAAUGCCUUUCUCCUUGAUGGGUGAUUGCGCCCGCUGGGAACUCUCAGAGAAGCGUGUCAACCUGGAACAAAAACUCAACUUCCUCUUCCAAGUCCUGGCCUUGGUUGCCCUCACACUGGUAGCAGGGAAGCUCACACACCUGAUACCCGUCUCGUGGAUGCCGGUCAUCUGGUCAGCCCUUUCGGCCGUCCUCCUCCUCGCAAGCUCCUAUUUUGUGGGUGCUCUGAUUGUCCAUGCCGAUUGCUUUCUGAUGAGAAACCACACCAUCACGGAGCAGCCCAUGUGCUUCCAAAGAACGACACCCCUUAUUCUGCAGGAGGUUGCGUCCUUUCUCAAAAGGAAUAAGCAUGGGCCUUUCCUCCUCUUUGUUUCCUUUCUACACGUUCACAUCCCUCUUAUCACUAUGGAGAACUUCCUCGGGAAGAGUCUCCACGGGCUGUAUGGGGACAACGUAGAGGAGAUGGACUGGAUGGUAGGACGGAUCCUUGACACUUUGGACGUGGAGGGUUUGAGCAACAGCACCCUCAUUUAUUUUACGUCGGAUCACGGCGGUUCCCUAGAGAAUCAACUUGGAAACACCCAGUAUGGUGGCUGGAAUGGAAUUUAUAAAGGUGGGAAGGGCAUGGGAGGAUGGGAAGGUGGGAUCCGCGUGCCCGGGAUCUUCCGCUGGCCCGGGGUGCUCCCGGCCGGCCGAGUGAUUGGCGAGCCCACGAGUCUGAUGGACGUGUUCCCCACCGUGGUCCGGCUGGCGGGCGGCGAGGUGCCCCAGGACAGAGUGAUUGACGGCCAAGACCUUCUGCCCUUGCUCCUGGGGACAGCCCAACACUCAGACCACGAGUUCCUGAUGCAUUAUUGUGAGAGGUUUCUGCACGCAGCCAGGUGGCAUCAACGGGACAGAGGAACAAUGUGGAAAGUCCACUUUGUGACGCCUGUGUUCCAGCCAGAGGGAGCCGGUGCCUGCUAUGGAAGAAAGGUCUGCCCGUGCUUUGGGGAAAAAGUAGUCCACCACGAUCCACCUUUGCUCUUUGACCUCUCAAGAGACCCUUCUGAGACCCACAUCCUCACACCAGCCUCAGAGCCCGUGUUCUAUCAGGUGAUGGAACGAGUCCAGCAGGCGGUGUGGGAACACCAGCGGACACUCAGCCCAGUUCCUCUGCAGCUGGACAGGCUGGGCAACAUCUGGAGACCGUGGCUGCAGCCCUGCUGUGGCCCGUUCCCCCUCUGCUGGUGCCUUAGGGAAGAUGACCCACAAUAAAUGUCUGCAGUGAAAAGCUGGAGCCCCGAUUCCUAAAUUUUGUCACUCAAAUUGAAACAAACCAGCUGGCCAUGGUGGUUGUCAUCCCAGCACUUUAGGAGGCCACCACAGGAGGAUCACUCCCGUGAUCAAAACCAACCUGGGCAACAUGAUGAAACUCUAGCUCUACAAAACAAAAAUAAAAAAAAAAUUAGCCUGCAUGGUGGCACACGCCUGUAGUUCUAGCUUCUCAGGAGGCUAAGGCAGGAGGAUCAUUUGAGCACCGGAGUUGGAGGCUGUACUGAGCUAUGAUUGUACCACUGCACCCCAGC